GCCUAUGAAGGGGACUGCCCAUGAAGUGAAAGUCAAGUGUGUGUUGCUGCGGCAGCCACGGAGGCCAAGGACCUCACGGGAGUAAAAGAUGACGAGACUGGCUUCGGGAGAAACACCAUCCAGAAGAGACCUUUCAAAAAACUUCUAGAGACUCCCCAAGACGUAUGAGAUGAAAGGCUUCUUCUGUCUGUGUGCGUUUAACUCAUUUCUCCUUAGCCCCGAGAUUACGCGCUGCUGUGCCUGCGACUGCAGCGUUUACGCCGAGAUAACUCGUGGAUUACAGUGCCAACCUUACUCCCAAAGUUUGCCACGAAAUAUCUCGCUUCUGUUAUUUUCGCAUGGUUCUGGUAUAUUGACUUUUGAAACAAAAGACAUCAUUCUGUUUAUAGCAUUCUGUUUUUAGUAGUGGGAUUUCCAUCUACAAAAUAUAGUAAUUCUCGAUCGCUGAAAUGUCAAAUCCUAGAAAACGUAGCAUUCCUAUGCGUGAUAGUAAUACCGGUCUCGAACAGUUGUUGGCUGAAGAUUCAUUUGAUGAAUCUGAUUUUUCGGAAAUAGAUGAUUCUGAUAAUUUUUCGGAUAGUGCUUUAGAAGCCGAUAAGAUCAGGCCUCUGUCCCAUUUAGAAUCUGAUGGAAAGAGCUCUACAUCAAGUGACUCAGGGCGCUCCAUGAAAUGGUCAGCUCGUGCUAUGAUUCCACGUCAAAGGUAUGACUUUACCGGCACACCUGGCAGAAAAGUCGAUGUCAGUGAUAUCACUGACCCAUUGCAGUAUUUUGAACUGUUCUUUACUGAGGAAUUAGUUUCAAAAAUUACUAGAGAAACAAAUGCCCAAGCUGCCUUGUUGGCUUCAAAGCCACCGGGUCCGAAAGGAUUUUCGCGAAUGGAUAAAUGGAAAGACACUGACAAUGACGAGCUCAAAGUCUUUUUUGCAGUAAUGUUACUGCAAGGUAUUGUGCAGAAACCUGAGCUGGAGAUGUUUUGGUCAACAAGGCCUCUUUUGGAUACACCUUAUCUCAGGCAAAUUAUGACUGGUGAAAGAUUUUUACUUUUGUUUCGGUGCCUGCAUUUUGUCAACAAUUCUUCUAUAUCUGCUGGUCAAUCAAAGGCCCAGAUUUCAUUGCAGAAGAUCAAACCUGUGUUCGACUUUCUUGUAAAUAAAUUUUCCACUGUAUAUACUCCAAACAGAAACAUUGCAGUUGAUGAAUCACUGAUGCUGUUCAAGGGGCCAUUAGCUAUGAAGCAGUACCUCCCGACAAAACGAGUACGAUUUGGUCUGAAGCUAUAUGUACUUUGUGAAAGUCAGUCUGGUUAUGUGUGGAAUGCGCUUGUUCACACAGGGCCUGGCAUGAAUUUGAAAGAUUCAGCGGAUGGCCUGAAAUCAUCACGCAUUGUUCUUACCUUGGUCAAUGACCUUCUUGGCCAAGGGUAUUGUGUCUUCCUCGAUAACUUUAAUAUAUCUCCCAUGCUUUUCAGAGAAUUACAUCAAAAUAGGACUGAUGCAGUUGGGACAGCUCGUUUGAACAGAAAACAGAUUCCAAAUGAUCUGAAAAAAAGGAUUGCAAAGGGGACGACUGUAGCCAGAUUCUGUGGUGAACUUAUGGCACUGAAAUGGUGUGACGGCAAGGAGGUGACAAUGUUGUCAACAUUCCACAAUGAUACUGUGAUUGAAGUAAACAAUAGAAAUGGAAAGAAAACUAAAAGGCCACGUGUCAUUGUGGAUUAUAACGAGAAUAUGGGAGCAGUGGACUCGGCUGAUCAAAUGCUUACUUCUUAUCCAUCUGAGCGCAAAAGACACAAGGUUUGGUAUAAGAAAUUCUUUCACCAUCUUCUACACAUUACAGUGCUGAACUCCUACAUCCUGUUCAAGAAGGAUAAUCCUGAGCACACGAUGAGCCAUAUAAACUUCAGACUGGCAUUGAUUGAAAGAAUGCUGGAAAAGCAUCACAAGCCAGGGCAGCAACAUCUUCGAGGUCGUCCUUGCUCCGAUGAUGUCACACCUCUUCGUCUGUCUGGAAGACAUUUCCCCAAGAGCAUACCAGCAACGUCCGGGAAACAGAAUCCAACUGGUCGCUGCAAAAUUUGCUGCUCCCAAUACGACAAGGAUGGCAAGAAGAUCCGGAAAGAAACGCGCUAUUUUUGUGCCGAAUGUGAUGUUCCGCUUUGUGUUGUUCCGUGCUUUGAAAUUUACCACACGAAAAAAAAUUAUUAAAUACCGAUCAUCAUACACAUCUGUUCCAUUAGGAUUAGAGACAAGUUCUGUUUAGAAAUAACUCCAAGAUUGGGAGGCCGACCUGGGUGGAUCACCUGAGAUCAGGAAUUCAAGACCAGCCUGGCCAACAUGGUGAAACCCUGUCUCUACUAAAAAUACAACAAUUAGCUGGAUGUGGUGGCACAUGCCUGUAAUCCAAGCUACUUGGGAGGCUGAGGCAGGAGAAUUGCUUGAACCCAUGAGGCGGAGGUUGCAGUGAGCUGAGAUCACACCACUGCACUCCAGCCUGGGUGACAUAGCGAGACUCCAUCUCAAAAAAAAGAAAUAACUCCAAGAACAGUUUUGUUGUUUUUGUUUUGUUUUGUUUUGUUUUGAGACGGAGUUUCACUCUUGUUGCCCAGGCUGGAGUGCAAUGGCAUGAUAUUGGCUCACUGUAACCUCCACCUCCCAGGUUCAAGCGAUUCUCGUGCCUCAGCCUCCCUAGUAGCUGGGAUUACAGGCAUGUGCCACCACACCCACCUAAUUUUGCAUUUUUAGUAGAGACUGGGUUUAUCCAUGUUGGUCAGGCUAGUCUUGACCUCCCGACCUCAGGUGAUCCGCCUAUCUGGGCCUCACAAAGUCCUGGGAUUAUAGGCAUGAGCCACUGCGCCUAGCACCAAGAACAGUUUUUAUAUUUUAUUUUCACAUUGAAAAUCAGUCAGAUUUGCUUCAGCCUCAAAGAGGGUGUUUAUGUAAAACUAAAUGAGUGCAGGCAGCGAGCUACACUUUUUUUUUUCCUAAAUGGAAAAUGGGAAGGAGAUACUGUCUCUGAACAAAAAUAGCUGGAAAAACACAUAACUGUUAACUAAGGGUUGCCUCUAGUGAAAAGGAUUGGAAGACAAUUUAUCUGAUGCUACACUAUUCUUCCUGUUGUGAUUGUUUUACUGUGAACAUAACAAGGUUGUAUUGGGGAGGAGGGCAGGGGUUGAUUGCUGCCAAUGUUGAUUGCUGAGGCCUUAGCCAAGAUUUCAGGCAUCAUUUGCUCCAGUCCUUUCAUUUUCUUUAUGGUGGAAAGUGAAGUGACUUGCCCAAGAUCUUUGUUGGCCCUAAACAUCGCUGUCUCUGCUACAGAUUCCUAUUGAGAGCAAUGCAUGUUUUAGCCUUGUGCACUCUUAGAGUCAGCAUCAUGGGAAAGAGUAACAGCAAUUGAAAAAAGAGAUUCAAGAGCCAAGUACUCAGCCCUGGCAGGGGAUGGGGACAUGAUGCCCAGAGCCACCCCUAUACUCCAGUCUCCCUGGCAUCAGCUACUGCAGUACUGGGGUACUUGCCUUCAUCUUUUUUCUGAAGAUAGUUACUUCUUCAUAUUUGAUCAUCGGAAGGAGCAGCAUUGCUCAGAAACACACACACACACACACACACUUGACUUUCUUGUCUGCCAAAUAAAUUUCUUAUUUGCUAGGGAACUGGUAAUCUAGGCUCAAGAAGUGUGUGGAGAAGGUUUAUUUUCAUUCUUUUUACUUUAAAAUAUGCCUUAGUUUUUGAAUAGAUAAGACAUUCAAGUGUCAGAAAGUAAAAGUCAGUUCAGGACUGAGAAAGGAAAGAUCAGUGCUGAUUUUAAUCAGACUGUAAUGUACCAACUAGAUACAGACAGGGCCAGUGGCAAGGCCAUCAGAAAACUUCUUCCCAAGGCCACACCACACCUGCAAAAUGCCUAACAACCUUCUUCUUUUCAGUGAUUACCACUUUCUUACCAAUGACUUCGCUUUGUUCCUCGUGCCUCUGAACAGACUGCUGAGAUACCCAAUCAAGAGCCAAUCCUUGCUUCCCUAGACUCUCCUCAAUCAUUCAACAGAAGCCCAAAUCUUGUAAAAGUUCCUUUCUGGGCCGGGCACAGUGGCUCACGCCUGUAAUCCCAGCACUUUGGAAGGCCGAGAUGGGCGAAUCACAAGGUCAGGAGUUUGAGACUAGCCUGGCCAACAUGGUGAAACCCUGUCUCUACUAAAAAUACAAAAAAAAAUUAGCUGGGCAUAGUGGUGGGUGCCUGUAAUCCCAGCUACUUGGGAGGCUGAGACAGGAGAAUCACUUGAACCCGGGAGGCAGAGGUUGCAGUGAGCCAAGAUCGCACCACUGCACUCCAGCCCUGGCGACAGAGUGAGACUCCAUCUCAAAAAAUAAAAAAGUUUCCUUCUGUUCCCUCUUACUGUUAUAUCCUUGGUUUCUCUGGUGUGGGGUCUUCCUUACAGCAGCAAGCUCAUAAACUUAACUUGACCGCAGGUGUGUUCCUUGGUGGUCUUUAUCUGAUAGACUUUGUCACAUGGUACAAUAUUCAAAAGGCACAUGGUACAAUAUUCAAAAGGCACAUGGUACAAUAUUCAAAAGGUAUGAGUAUACAAAAAAAAUCUCCCACCUACUUCUCUCCCUAGUCACCCAAUUCUCAAGAGGCAAUCACUGUUGCCAUUUUCCUGAGUAUUCUUCCACAGAUAGUCAACUAUCUACAGAAAAAUAUAUACAUUAAAAAUAAGGCCAGGCACAGUGGCAUGCCUGUAGUCCCAGCUACUCAGAAGGUUGAAGCAGGAGGAUCACUUGAGGCCAGGAGGGCCAGGAAUUUGAAGCUGUAGUGUGCUAUGAUAGCAGGCCUGUGAAUAGCCAUUGCACUCCAUCCUGGGCAACAUAGCCAGACCCUGUCUCUAAAAAAAAAAAAAAAAAAAAAAAAGACAAAAAAACAAAUCCAUAUAUACAUAUAUAUGUAUAUAUAUAGUAUGCUACCAGUUGUGUGAAAAAAGGGGCAAAAUAUAUAUUUAUUUAACUUAUAUACAAAUAACAUUCUAGAAAUAAAUUGUUUAAUAUAAAAUACACUAAUAUAUAAUAAUGUAUUACCUAACAUAUGAUUAUAUAUAACUAUAAUGUGUACUGUUUUACAUACAUAUUUCCAAAGUAUACUAUAAAUGCACUUCCGCACUUUGCUCUUUUUACUAAAUAUAUCUUGGAAAUCAUCCUUUAUUCGUACAUAAAAAGCUUCAUAGUUCCUUUUUAUGGCUGCAAAAUGUUCCAGCUUAUGGAUGGACUGAUUCUCUAUCGAGCAACAUUAAGAUUGUGUCCUAUUUUACUAUUCCUAAUUUUGCUGAAGUGAAUUUCUUUUGCCAUGUGAUUUCCACAGGUGUAUAUAUGUAGCGUAAUUAGUACUAGUAGAAAGUAGAAUUGCUAGAUCAAAGAGUAUGUGCCUUUGUAAUUUUGAUGAUAUUGUGAAAUCUUCUUCCACAGAAGUUGUUGCAACUUUCACUCUCACCAGCAAUGUGUAAGAUAACUUGCUUCUUCAUACCCUCACCAACAAUGAGCUAUCAAAUGUUAUUUUUGCCAAGCAAAUAAAUUAAAAGUGAUAUCUCAGUUUUUGUUUGUUUGUUUGUUUUUUGAGACAGAGUUUCACUCUUUGUUGCCCAGGCUGGAGUGCAGUGGCGUGAUCUCGGCUCACUGUAACCUCCGCCUCCCAGGUUCAAACGAUUCUCCUGUCUCACCCUCCCGAGUAGCUGGGAUUACAGGCACCUGCCACCACACCCAGUUAAUUUUUGUAUUUUUAGUAGAGACAGGGUUUCACCAUGUUGGCUAGGCUGACCUCGAACUCCUAACCUCAGGUGAUCCACCUGCCUCGGCCUCCCAAAGUGCUGGAAUUACAGGCGUGAGCCACCAUGCCUGGCUCUUCUUGCUUGUUUGUUUUGAGACAGAGUCUUGCUCUGUCAGCCAGGCUGGAGUGCAGUGGCACGAUAUUGGCUCACUGCAACCUCUGUCUCCCAGGCUCAAGCAAUUCUCCUGCCUCAGCCUCCUGAGUAGCUAGGAUUACAGAUGUGUGCCACCACGCCUGGCUAAUUUUUGUACUUUUAGUAGAGACGGAGUUUCACCAUGUUGGCCAGGCUGGUCUCAAACUCCUGACCUCAGGUAAUCCGCCUGCCUUGGCCUCCCAAAGUGCUGGGAUGACAGGCGUGAGCCACCACGCUGGGCCUCUUCUUGGUUUUUUAAUCCAUCUUCUGCCAUAUGGUGAAUUAAAUCUAAGUUGUAUUGUAGGAUUAAUGGAGAGCAGCUAAAGAGGAAUAAAGCCAUGUGUUCAGCCAAGGAUAGUUAUCAUGAAGGAUAAAAGCCUCAAAAUCCUGAUUUUGAAAUACAAAGUGCUGAUUUUAAAAUCAGUACAUGUUGAGCUGAGCCCUGAGGCCUUUGUUUCAGUCCCAACCAGAGCAGAAGUAAGCAUUGUUGAAACCGUAGUAAAAAGAUUAUUUGAGAAAUAAUGGAAUGGGACAAAGGAUUAUAAUGUGCUACAGCCCUCUGACCAUUACACUUUCUAAACUAUUAAUAAAAUUUUACUUUUCAAAAAUGAUUUCAAAAAUUGCAAAAUUUAGAAAUAUGCUGAAAUAAAAACAGCUUCAUCCCAA